GCAAGGCUGCUGCUAUGGGGCCGGGCGGCCGUGUGGCGCGGCUGCUCGCCCCACUAAUGUGGCGCAGGGCGGUUUCCUCGGUGGCGGGGUCCGCGGUUGGAGCCGAGCCCGGGCUUCGGCUGCUGGCCGUGCAGCGGCUUCCCGUAGGAGCAGCGUUCUGCCGGGCUUGCCAGACCCCAAACUUUGUCCGCGGCCUGCACAGCGAGCCUGGGCUGGAGGAGCGGGCGGAGGGGACGGUCAACGAGGGACGCCCAGAAUCGGACGCGGCAGAUCAUACUGGUCCCAAGUUUGACAUCGAUAUGAUGGUUUCACUUCUGAGGCAAGAAAAUGCAAGAGACAUUUGUGUGAUCCAGGUUCCUCCAGAAAUGAGAUAUACAGAUUACUUUGUGAUUGUUAGUGGAACUUCUACCCGACACUUACAUGCCAUGGCCUUCUACGUUGUGAAAAUGUACAAACACCUGAAAUGUAAACGUGACCCUCAUGUUAAGAUAGAAGGGAAGGACACUGAUGACUGGCUGUGCGUGGAUUUUGGCAGCAUGGUGAUUCAUUUGAUGCUUCCAGAAACCAGAGAAAUCUAUGAAUUAGAGAAAUUAUGGACCCUACGUUCUUAUGAUGACCAGUUAGCUCAGAUAGCACCUGAGACAGUACCUGAAGACUUCAUUCUUGGAAUAGAAGAUGAUACUUCAUCUGUGACUCCAGUGGAGUUAAAAUGUGAAUAAAAUAUUUUAUGCACUGCGUUAGUCAUUUCAGAUUUGGAUUGAGUCACUUAUUGGAAAAUACAGCUCCUAAAGUCCGUCUCCUUGGUUAGGCUGCUCUUAGGACAAGGCUUGUGUACCUCAUGGGCACUCCUGCUAACUGGCAUGCAGAGACUGUCGAUAAGUGAGCUAUACCUGCAACCAAAAAUCAGUACAUUCUACCCAAAACUUAUGACACGCUGCCUUUAUCCUGGAAAUGUCAUCAGAAUUUCCUGGAGUUAGCACUGGCUCCUGUGCUUGACUUCUCUGCUCAGAUUUUUAUUAAUUUAAUUUAGCUUAAAUGUAAAUCUUAACCCUGUUUGUUUAAUGGAAUGGCAAAAAUUUUAAAAAAUAAUAUAAAACAUAGCCCACUGGUCUUAUUUUUAUACUUUGAGGUGAUAAUAUUCUUCUAGGAGGACUUCUGUAACCCUUCCAGAAUACUCCAGUAACACAAGAAAGUAAACAAAGUGUUUGUUAGGAAAAACUCUGAACGCUCUAGUUCUUAGUUCAUAUGCAAGAGUAUUAUCAAGGUUCACAUUAAGUACCAUGGCUGGACAUGGUAUAACAGAAAUCUGCGUAGAGUUUGAAAAAAAAUUCAGAACAUUCCCAUUCAAUUGAAAACCAAAAAUAAAACAUACUACACAACAAGCUGCACCUAAAUGAUGAAAAAAUUUAUUCUGCGUCAAGGUAUCUGGAAAAUGAAGCUGCAUUUGGGGCACAUUAUACAUGAGGAAUGAUCCAUAUAUGGUGAGUACAAAACUCAAUUAUAGAAUUAUUUCUUAGCUAGUACCAGAUACUCCAAAUUACAAAUGCUUAAGUAAAAGUAAAAUAUGAUUUGCCAUACUAAAAGGCUAGAAGUGAAAUAUGACAGAAUUUAAACCAGCAGAUAUAAAUGCAGCACCUAUGUGUAUAUUUUUAAAAAAUCAAAUAUUGGGGAAAAAAAUCAAAUACUGAGAAAAGCUCUGGCCUUAAACACAUCUUACCUGAAAUCCAACCAGAAAGCCAGUCCAUGAUUUUAGCAAUUUUAAUUCAUUGUAUGAAAAAAAAAUCAUGAAUGCUAGGAGAAUCCAGUGACAAAAAGGGCACUUUUUUGGUUAAAACUACAAAAGAAACUUGUUUUCAGAGAACAUUAAGGAAAACACUUUAAAUCAUUUUCAAAAUGUCUAAUUGAUCUUCAGAAAAACAUCUAGUCUGUAUAGAAAUUCAUCUUGAAAUAAGAAUGAGGCAGUGAUUUUUUUUUUAAAGGGUUAUAUAUAUGUCCUUUAGAUCAGUGUAACAUGACUGUGAUCAUCUUACAAACAAAACUCAAAAAAUCAAUUCAGAGAGCAGCGUGGCCUUGGAGACCACCCACACCCAACACAAUUGUACGUACUGGGCUUUGCUGUCAAGGAGUGAGCAAAUGAGUUCGUUAUCAAAGGUCAUAUGUUUUCACAGUCAUUCAAAUUAUAUCCCAAAAACUUUUCUUGUAUUCUCUAUCUUUUGACUUUUUUUUCAAAGAACUGAUUGCACAGUAUACAGAAAUCCUGUUAUACUUUACUACUUAAGGUGGAGUCUAAUUUUUUUUUUUUAAUUUAUCAGUGCUUAAAAAUCUUCAAAAUAGCUUAGUGAGGCUCAUGACAGUGCUGGCCCCAUGGAAAUGUAGCCUUUUGUUGCGUUUAAACACUGUCACACCAUCUAUGACUGUCCCAUUGGUCUGAAGUGUAGUGGCAAACUAAGCAUCCUAUAAGACAAGCUAAAGCUUGCUUUUUGCCAGUCAGUUGAAAGUCUUGCAUCUCUUCACUGAUGCACUUUCUUUAGGUAUUGAUAGUCAGAAGCACAAAGCAUUUAUUAUGCAUUCAAUCAUGUAGCUAAACAAAAAACUGAAGUCUCCUGAAGCCAUUUAAACCAGCCGUUCCAAAAUCUCCUGCGACCACUUUGUUAGUACCGUCAAAAACUUUCCCAACUAUAAAUGAAAGAAUAAAUGGUAGUGCUGCUCUCCAGAUACUAGGCACUGCUCCGUAUUUUUGAACAUUUGAUUUAACUAAUAACUGUGUCAAAAGCCUCAAAAAACCCUGAAAUUAAUUUUCCAGCUUUACUGUCACCAGCCAGAAGUAAAAAUCUUAAUUUGCCUGUUAGCUGAUUGCUGUUAAAUUUUAAAUUUAUUUUUUAAAAAACGGUUGGACUUCUAUCAU